AGUAGCGACCAUUUCCAUUGGCGUUAGGGAGUCCUUGGAGCGCUGUGUUGGGACCGUGGUGGUGACUGGAUCCAGGAGGUCGAGAGUCGUUCUUCUCUUUGCACAGACGUGACUCUGCAGCUCUUUAACGGCGCCCGCUGCUCUCAACCCAGCUUACCCCACGUGGUCCCAUGGCGGCGGCCGCGCUAAGGUUCCCCGUUCAGGUAAUUGUGGCGCCUUCCGUGCUCUCCGGUCACCUCCUAGUCACACAAGUCCUAAAGCAGCGAGGGAGCGGCACCUGUUUACGGCUCUGCAACCCGGACCCGGCGUCGGGACACUGAGGCGCUCUCGGGAGGGAUCCCUGUUUCAGACACCCGUGGGAUGCGGUGGGGAGAGCGACAGGGCACAGUGACUUUUGAAGACGUGGCUGUGAAAUUUACCCAGGAGGAAUGGAAUCUCCUUAGUGAGGCUCAGAGAUGCCUGUACCGUGAUGUGACGCUGGAGAACCUGGCACUUAUGUCCUCCCUGGGUUGUUGGUGUGGAGUGGAAGAUGAGGCGGCACCUUCUAAGCAGAGUAUUUAUAUACAAAGAGAGACUCAGGUCAGGACUCCUAUGGCAGGUGUGUCUCCCAAGAAGGCCCACCCCUGUGAGAUGUGUGGCCCGAUCUUGGGAGACAUUUUGCAUGUGGCAGAUCAUCAGGGAACACAUCACAAGCAGAAACUGCACAGGUGUGAGGCCUGGGGGAAUAAAUUGUAUGACAGUGGAAACUUUCAUCAGCACCAGAAUGAGCACAUUGGAGAGAAACCCUACAGAGGGAGUGUUGAGGAGGCGUUGUUUGCGAAGAGGUGUAAGUUGCAUGUGUCAGGGGAGUCAUCUGUCUUCAGUGAGAGUGGGAAAGACUUUUUGCUCAGGUCAGGAUUACUCCAGCAAGAGGCCACUCACACUGGGAAGUCAAACAGCAAAACUGAGUGUGUGUCUCUGUUUCAUGGGGGAAAAAGCCAUUACAGCUGUGGAGGAUGCAUGAAACAUUUUAGCACCAAAGAUAUACUCAGUCAGCACGAGAGACUGCUCCCUACAGAAGAACCUUCUGUGUGGUGUGAAUGUGGGAAAUCCUCUAGCAAAUAUGACAGCUUCAGUAAUCAUCAAGGAGUUCACACUAGAGAAAAACCUUAUACGUGUGGGAUAUGUGGGAAAUUAUUUAACAGUAAGUCCCACCUCCUUGUACACCAGAGAAUUCACACUGGAGAGAAGCCAUAUGAGUGUGAGGUUUGUCAGAAAUUUUUUAGGCACAAGUACCACCUCAUUGCACACCAGAGAGUUCACACUGGAGAAAGGCCAUAUGAAUGCAGUGAUUGUGGGAAGUCAUUUACCCACAGCUCUACAUUCCGUGUUCAUAAGAGAGUUCACACUGGUCAGAAGCCUUAUGAGUGCAGUGAAUGUGGGAAAUCUUUUGCCGAAAGCUCCAGUCUCACUAAACACAGGAGAGUUCACACUGGAGAAAAGCCUUACGGGUGCAGUGAAUGUGAAAAAAAAUUUAGGCAAAUCUCUUCACUUCGUCAUCAUCAGAGAGUUCACAAAAGAAAGGGCUUAUGAGUGCAGUGAGUCCAGUCUCAUUAAAUAUUGGAGAAUACACACCUGAGUAAGAUCCUGUGAUUGCAGCAAAUGUGGAAAAUGUUUACCCAAAGGUCUGCUCUCCUUGGAUAUUGGAGAGUUCACACUAGAGAAGAGUCCUUACAAGUAAAAUAAAUUUGGGCAGUUUUGUAGCCACACCUCUGUAUUCCUUCAGGAUUAUAGUUAACACUGAAUGAAGGCCUUACUAGUGUGACAAAUACAGGAUAUUUAUCCAGAAGUCUGGCUGCAUAACUCACAGGAGAGCUGUCAUGUGGGAGGAUUGCUACAUGGGAGGAUUUGCUUGAGCCUGGGAGGCAGAGGUUGCAGUGAGCCGAGAUUGCAACACUGCAGUCCAGUCUGGACCACAGAGUGAGACCCUGUUUCAAAAAUAAAAUAUAUAAAUGACAUCCAAUAAAGUAUGCAUAUUUGAGCUGUAGGAUAAGUCUUGAAUUUUCUUUUUCUUUUUUUUGAGACAGCCUCGCUCUGUCACCCAGGCUGGAGUACAGUGGCAUAAUCUCGGCUCACUGCAAGCCCUGCCUCCUGGGUUCAUGCCAUUCUCCUGCCUCAGCCUCCCUAAUAGCUGGGACUACAGGCAACCACCACCACUCCUACCUUUUUUGUAUUUUUAGUAGAGAUGGGGUUUCACCCUGUUAGCCAGGAAGUUCUCAAUCUCCUGACCUCGUGAUCUGCCCGCCUUGGCCUCUCAAAGUGUUGGGAUUGCAGGCGUGAGCCACUGCUCCUGGCUUGAAUUUUCUUAUAAUCCCAUGAAACCAUCAUCAGAGUCACAAUAAUGAAUUUAUCUAAUCUAUCACCUUUGUAUUCACCUGGAGCCUUUAUAAAGUUUUUCUCUAUGCAGACAACCAUUGAUUUACUCUGCUGUAUAAUACUUUCCAUUUUCUAGAAUUUUCUGACUGAUGUAAUAAAGUGUUUCCUCUUAUAA